AGGGCGAGGCUGAGGGCAGAGAGUUGGACACAACCCUGAGAUUUAUCCCUCACAAUGCGGAAAGACAGACUUCUUCAUUUAUGUCUUGUGCUACUUCUUAUCCUGCUUUCUGCCAGUGACUCAAACUCUACAGAACCGCAGUAUAUGGUGCUGGUCCCCUCCCUGCUCCACACUGAGGCCCCUAAGAAGGGCUGUGUCCUUCUGAGCCACCUGAAUGAGACAGUGACUGUAAGUGCUUCCUUGGAGUCUGGCAGGGAAAACAGGAGCCUCUUCACUGACCUGGUGGCGGAGAAGGACUUAUUCCACUGUGUCUCCUUCACUCUCCCAAGGAUCUCAGCCUCUUCAGAGGUGGCAUUCCUUAGCAUCCAGAUAAAGGGGCCUACGCAAGAUUUCAGGAAGAGGAACACAGUUCUGGUACUGAACACCCAAAGUCUGGUCUUUGUCCAGACAGACAAACCCAUGUAUAAACCAGGACAGACAGUAAGAUUCCGUGUUGUCUCCGUGGAUGAAAAUUUUCGCCCUCGAAAUGAACUGAUUCCACUGAUAUACCUUGAGAACCCAAGAAGAAAUCGAAUUGCACAAUGGCAGAGUCUCAAGCUAGAAGCUGGCAUCAAUCAGUUGUCCUUUCCCCUCUCAUCAGAGCCCAUUCAGGGCUCCUACAGGGUGGUGGUACAGACAGAAUCAGGUGGAAGGAUACAGCACCCCUUCACCGUGGAGGAAUUUGUGCUUCCCAAGUUUGAGGUCAAAGUUCAGGUGCCAAAGAUAAUCAGUAUCAUGGAUGAAAAAGUGAACAUAACAGUCUGUGGAGAAUACACUUAUGGGAAGCCUGUCCCAGGACUUGCAACUGUGAGCCUGUGUAGAAAAUUAUCUCGUGUUCUUAAUUGUGACAAGCAGGAGGUCUGUGAGGAAUUCAGUCAACAGCUUAACAGCAAUGGCUGCAUCACCCAACAAGUACACACCAAAAUGCUCCAGAUUACAAAUACGGGCUUUGAAAUGAAGCUUAGAGUGGAAGCCAGGAUCAGAGAAGAGGGGACAGACCUGGAAGUCACUGCAAACAGGAUCAGUGAAAUCACAAACAUUGUAUCCAAACUCAAAUUCGUGAAAGUGGAUUCACACUUUAGACAAGGAAUCCCCUUUUUUGCACAGGUGCUUCUGGUGGAUGGAAAAGGUGUGCCCAUCCCCAAUAAACUCUUCUUCAUCUCUGUGAAUGACGCCAAUUAUUACUCCAAUGCAACCACCAAUGAGCAGGGUCUUGCACAGUUUUCAAUCAAUACUACCAGUAUCUCGGUUAAUAAACUUUUUGUCCGGGUUUUCACUGUGCAUCCCAACUUGUGUUUUCACUAUUCAUGGGUAGCAGAAGACCACCAGGGUGCUCAGCACACUGCAAAUCGUGUUUUCUCCUUAAGUGGAAGUUACAUUCACCUGGAGCCUGUGGCUGGUACCCUGCCCUGUGGCCACACGGAGACUAUCACGGCACACUAUACACUGAAUAGACAGGCCAUGGGAGAGUUAUCGGAGCUCAGUUUCCAUUACCUGAUCAUGGCUAAGGGAGUCAUCGUCAGAUCUGGAACCCACACUCUGCCUGUGGAGUCAGGAGACAUGAAAGGCAGUUUUGCCUUAUCCUUCCCUGUGGAGUCAGACGUUGCCCCCAUUGCACGAAUGUUCAUCUUUGCCAUUUUACCAGAUGGAGAAGUUGUUGGAGACUCUGAAAAAUUUGAGAUUGAAAACUGUCUAGCCAACAAGGUGGAUUUGAGCUUCAGCCCAGCACAAAGUCCCCCAGCCUCACAUGCCCACCUGCAAGUAGCAGCUGCUCCGCAGUCCCUCUGUGCCCUUCGUGCUGUGGACCAAAGUGUGCUGCUCAUGAAGCCUGAGGCUGAGCUCUCUGUGUCCUCAGUAUAUAAUCUGCUAACUGUGAAGGAUCUCACCAAUUUUCCUGACAAUGUGGACCAGCAGGAGGAAGAACAAGGACACUGUCCCCGUCCUUUCUUCAUUCAUAAUGGAGCCAUCUAUGUUCCCUUAUCAAGUAAUGAAGCAGAUAUUUAUAGCUUCCUCAAGGGGAUGGGAUUGAAGGUGUUCACUAACUCAAAAAUCCGAAAACCAAAGUCGUGUUCAGUCAUCCCUUCCGUGUCUGCAGGAGCAGUAGGUCAAGGAUACUAUGGAGCAGGUCUAGGAGUAGUAGAGAGACCAUAUGUUCCUCAAUUAGGCACAUAUAAUGUGAUACCCUUAAAUAAUGAACAAAGUUCAGGGCCAGUCCCUGAAACGGUGCGAAGCUAUUUUCCUGAGACUUGGAUCUGGGAGUUGGUGGCAGUGAACUCAUCAGGUGUGGCUGAGGUAGGAGUAACAGUCCCUGACACCAUCACCGAGUGGAAGGCAGGGGCCUUCUGCCUGUCCGAAGAUGCUGGACUUGGUAUCUCUUCCACUGCCUCUCUCCGAGCCUUCCAGCCCUUCUUUGUGGAGCUCACAAUGCCUUACUCUGUGAUUCGUGGAGAGGUCUUCACACUCAAGGCCACGGUCCUAAACUACCUUCCCAAAUGCAUCCGGGUCAGUGUGCAGCUGAAAGCCUCUCCAGCCUUCCUAGCUUCCCAAAAUACAAAGGGAGAAGAAUCCUAUUGUAUCUGUGGAAAUGAGAGACAAACCUUGUCUUGGACAGUGACUCCUAAAACUCUGGGGAAUGUGAACUUCUCAGUGAGUGCAGAGGCAAUGCAGUCCUUAGAACUCUGUGGAAAUGAGGUUGUUGAGGUCCCUGAGAUUAAAAGAAAAGACACAGUCAUCAAAACCCUGUUGGUGGAGGCUGAAGGUAUUGAGCAAGAAAAGACUUUCAGUUCUAUGACCUGUGCCUCAGGUGCUAAUGUGUCUGAGCAGUUGUCCUUGAAGCUCCCAUCAAAUGUGGUCAAAGAAUCUGCCAGAGCUUCUUUCUCAGUUCUGGGUGACAUAUUAGGUUCUGCUAUGCAAAAUAUACAAAAUCUCCUCCAGAUGCCAUAUGGCUGUGGAGAACAGAACAUGGUCCUAUUUGCUCCUAACAUCUAUGUCUUGAACUAUCUGAAUGAAACCCAGCAGCUGACGCAGGAGAUCAAGGCCAAGGCCGUUGGCUAUCUCAUCACUGGUUACCAGAGACAGCUGAACUACAAACACCAAGAUGGCUCCUACAGCACCUUUGGGGAACGAUAUGGCAGGAACCAGGGCAACACUUGGCUCACAGCUUUUGUACUGAAGACUUUCGCCCAGGCUCGAUCCUACAUCUUCAUUGAUGAAGCACACAUUACCCAAUCUCUCACGUGGCUCUCCCAGAUGCAGAAGGACAAUGGCUGUUUCAGGAGCUCUGGGUCACUGCUCAACAAUGCCAUAAAGGGAGGUGUAGAAGAUGAAGCGACCCUCUCCGCCUAUGUUACUAUUGCCCUUCUGGAAAUUCCUCUCCCAGUCACUAACCCUAUUGUUCGCAAUGCCCUGUUCUGCCUGGAGUCAGCCUGGAAUGUAGCAAAGGAGGGGACCCAUGGGAGCCAUGUCUACACCAAGGCAUUGCUGGCCUAUGCUUUUUCCCUACUGGGAAAGCAAAAUCAGAAUAGAGAAAUACUGAACUCACUUGAUAAGGAAGCUGUGAAAGAAGACAACCUCGUCCAUUGGGAGCGCCCUCAGAGACCCAAGGCACCAGUGGGGCAUCUUUACCAAACCCAGGCUCCCUCUGCUGAGGUGGAGAUGACAUCCUAUGUGCUCCUCGCUUAUCUCACGGCCCAGCCAGCCCCCACCUCAGGGGACCUGACCUCUGCAACUAACAUUGUGAAGUGGAUCAUGAAGCAGCAGAACGCCCAAGGUGGUUUCUCCUCCACCCAGGACACAGUGGUGGCUCUCCAUGCCCUGUCCAGGUAUGGAGCAGCCACUUUCACCAGAACUGAGAAAACUGCACAGGUCACCGUUCAGGAUUCACAGACCUUUUCUACAAAUUUCCAAGUAGACAACAACAACCUCCUAUUACUGCAGCAGAUCUCAUUGCCAGAGCUCCCUGGAGAAUAUGUCAUAACAGUAACUGGGGAAAGAUGUGUGUAUCUUCAGACAUCCAUGAAAUACAAUAUUCUUCCAGAGAAAGAGGACUCCCCAUUUGCUUUAAAAGUGCAGACUGUGCCCCAAACUUGCGAUGGACACAAAGCCCACACCAGCUUUCAGAUCUCACUGACCAUCAGUUACACAGGAAACCGUCCUGCUUCCAAUAUGGUGAUUGUUGAUGUAAAGAUGGUAUCUGGUUUUAUUCCCCUGAAACCAACAGUAAAAAUGCUUGAAAGAUCUAGCUCUGUGAGCCGGACAGAAGUGAGCAACAACCAUGUCCUCAUUUAUGUGGAACAGGUGACAAAUCAGACGCUAAGUUUUUCCUUCAUGGUUCUGCAAGACAUCCCAGUAGGAGACUUGAAGCCAGCAAUUGUUAAAGUCUAUGAUUACUAUGAGACAGGUAUUAAAGACCCUAAAAUGACUUCUGGUGGCCUGGGAUUCCUUGGGAAAACAGAAAAGUUGCCACAAAUCCCAUUUGGGGAAAAACCUUUGUUUUCGUUGUGGAACCCCUGGAAUUAGAGAACAUGAUUUGAAAAACUGGUUAUUUUACCAAGGCUUUGACUGGAGAGGUGUGCUGUCCUUUAAGGAAUCAAACUUGACUUAUGGAGCCAAUAAAACUCUCGGGAAACUGGCCUCAUAUUUUAUGUGCACAGUCCCUGUACAGGGUUUCUGACCUGUGGUAAGUAAAGAAUGUCACUUUCUGACAGGCCAGUACCCCCAAGUUAUCUUGGAACCUCAGGAGGAGAGGAAUUCACCCAACUCAUAGGUAUUUAAUGGUACAAUUCCAUGACUGGGCUCAGCUUUAAAAGGCCUUAUCUCAGAUUCCUUCUAUGGAACAAAAUUCCAUCAAUGCCAGUUUAAAAGGCCUAGGUAACAAAUAAUUAUUCUUGCUGCACUGUAUGCAAAUAAUUAAACCAAGUAUAAUAAUGCAAACCAUUCCUACCAUGAUUUAUUUUUUAAUAACGGUUACUGGCAGAAAAUAACACGUGGCCCUUUCCAAACAUGUGCCUCUGCCUCUCAUUAGGUAAGGAAUGUUGCUUCUAUCUCAACCAAUUGGGCCGAGUAAGAAACACUGCUAAAUAACUUAAAGAAAGGGCCAAAGAGCUAAGGGAAUUCCAAAACAACCAAAUGGAUUCUUGAUUUGGGAAAAAAACCAUAGCAUGGGUCAUCCCAUUCCUGGGCCCCCCCCUACUACUAUGCCUAGGACUAAUGUUCUUACCCUGCCUAAUUAAUCUUUUCCAGAGAUUUUUAACUGACAGGAUCAUGGCCAUUUCACAGACAACUACCCAAAAACUGCCCCAAAGGGCAUCAGCCUAAUGGCUAAUGUCAGCAUGACCAUAAACCACAAAUGACAUCUCUGACCAGAAACAUUCCAACACGAAAAUAAACCCCUCCCCAGCCAGAGACAUGCCCAUCCCAAGAUAACCUCCUCUCCGGCCAGAGAGAUGCAGCCCCAAGAUAACCUCCCCUCUGACCAGAGACAUUCCAACCCCACAAUAAACUUCUCCUCCACACAGAAACAUUCCAAGCCUGUGAUAAGCUCUCUUACCCUAAAACCCUUAAAUACUCUUAGUCUGUAAGAGAGAGUGGUCCUGACCAAAAAUUGGUCAGAAUCCCCUCUCAGGUUUAUUCUCCAAAAUAAACCUGUCUUUCACUGUUGAGCCAUUUUUCAUGUUUCUUUCCUCUUUCUUUAACUCUUACAGGAGGAGUGGCUACACUUAUAUCAGAUAAAAUAGACUGAGUUAAAAACUGUUACAAGAGACCAAAAGGGAAAUUUUAUAAUGAUAAAAGGGUCAAUUCAACAGGAAUAUAUAACAAUUACAAUUAUAUAUGCAUCCAACAGUAGAACACCUAAAUAUAUAAAGCAAACAUUGGAAAAACAGAAAAGAGAAAUAGGGAGCAAUAAAAUAAUAGUAGGAAACUUCAAUACUAUUUGCAAUAAUGGAUACAUCAUUCAGACAGAAAUCUGUAUCCAUAAGAAAACAGCAGACUUGAAUAACACAAUAGACCAAAUGGACCAAACAGACAUAUGCAGAAUAUUCCACCAAACAGCAGCUGAAUACAUACUCUUCUCAUGUGCACUCAGAUCCUUCCCCAGGAUAAGUCACAUAUUAAGUCACAAAAUAAGUUAUAACAAAUUUAGAAAGAUUGAAAUCACACCAAGUGUCUUUCUGGCCACAACAAAAUUAAACUAUAAAUCAAUAACAGAAGGAAGACUGGAAAAAUAAAAAAUACAUAGAUAUUAAACAACAGACUCUUGAAAAGUCAUUGAGUGAAAGAAGGAAUCAAGAAGGAAUUUAAAGUGCCUUAAUACAAAUGAAAACAAAAAUAAAAAACACUAAAAUUAUGGUAUUCAGCAAAAGCACUAUUAAGAAGGAGGUUUACUGUGAUAAAUACCUACAUUAACAAAGAACAAAGAUCUAAAAUAAUCAACCCAAAUUUAUACUUCAAGAGGCUAGAAAAAGAACAAACUAAGCUCAAAAUUAGCAGAGAAAGAAAUAACAAAAAUUAGAGAAGAAAUAAAUAAAACAAGAAAAGAAAAAAAUCAAAGAGGCUCAGUGGGUUUUUUGAAAAAAAUAAUUAACACACCCUUAUUUAGACUAAAAAAAAAGAAAUGAAAGAAGAUACAUUAUAACUGCUCUUUUAGAAAUAAAAAUGAUCAUAAGUGAACAAAUAUGUCAACUAAUCGAAUAACCUAGAAGAAUUGUGUAAAUUCCCAAAUACACAAAACAUGUCAAAAGUAAAAAUCAAGAAAGUUUGAACAGACCUAUCAUUAGUAUGGAGAUUUAAUGAAUAACAAAAAUCCUUCUAACAAAUAAAAACCCAGGAUCAGAUAGCUUCACAGGUAGAUUCUAAUACACAUUUUUUUAAAAAAGUGCCAAUCAGUCUCAAAUGCUUCCAAAAAGUGAGAGAACACUUCCAAACUCAUUUUAUAAGGCCAGUAGCACACUGCUACCAAAGCCAGACAAGGACACUACAAGAAAAAAAAAAUGACAGGCCAAUAUCUCUGAUGAAUAUAGAUGCAAAAAAUAUUUUAAAAAUAUUAGGAAAUAGAAUCCAACAGCACAUUAAAGGGAUCAUACAUCAUGACCAAGUAGUAUUUAUUCCCAGGAUGCAAGGAUGGUUCAGUAUGUAUAAAUUUGUACCACAUUCACAGAAUAAAGGGAAAAAAAAUCACAUAAUUAUAUAAAUACAAGCAGAGAAAGCAUUUGACAAAAUUCAACAUUCUUUCAUGUUAAAAACUCUCAAGAAACUAUAAAUAGGAGAGUAUCUCAACAUAAUACAGGCUAUAUAUGAAAGGCCCAUAGAUAAUAUCAGACUCAACGGUGAAAAGUUGAAAGCUUUUCCUUUAAGAACAGGAGCAAGGCAAUGAUGCCCACUCUUGCCACUUUUAUUCAAUAUAGAACCAAAGCCCUAGCCAGAACAGUUAGGUAAGAAAAAUAAAUUAAAGCCUACCAAAUCAGAAAGGAAGAGAUAAACUUUUUCCUGUUUGCUGAUGCCAUUAUAUUAUGUAUUAAAAAUCCCAAAGGCUCCAUUUUAAAAAACUGUUAAAACUAAUACACAAAUACAGUAAGAUUGCAAGCUACAAAAUCAACUUACAAAAAUCAGUUGCAUUUCUAUACACUAGCAAUAAACUCUGAAAAGGAAAUUAAGACAACAAUCCCAUUUACAAUAGCACAAAAAAGAAUUAAAUACUUAAGGAAAAACUUUUCCAAGGAAGUGAAAGACCUGUGUCUGGAAACAAAAACAUUGAUGAAAGAAAUUAAGACACAAUUAAAUAAAAAUAUAUACCAUGUUCAUUGAUUGGAAGAUUUACUAUUGUCAAAAUAACCAUAAUAUCAAAAGCAAUCUAUAGAUUCAAUGCAACCCCUGUCAAAAUCACAUUGGUAUUGUUUAAAAAAAUAGAAAAGGAAAUCCUAAAAUUUAUAGGGAAUGAGAAAACACCACAAAUAACAAAAUCAAUCUUGAGAAAGAAGAAGAAAGCUGGAGGACUCACACUUCCUAAUUUCAAAAUUUAGUACAAAACCACAGUAAUCAAAACAGUAUGGUGCUGGCAUAAAGACAGAUAAACAUCAAUGACAGAAUAGAGAUCUCAGGAAUAAAUGCACCCAUAAAAGGUCAACUGGUCUUUGACAAGGGUACCAAGAAUACACUAGGGGGAAUGGAUAGUCCCUUCAACAAAUGGUGUGGAGAAAACUGUAUAUCCAUAAGCAAAACAAUAAAAUUUGAUGUUUAUCUUACACCAUACACAAGAAUUAACUCAAAGUGGAUUAAAGACAUAAAAGUAAGGCCUGAAACUGUAAAACUGAUAUAAGAAAAAAUAAAAGACAUGCUUUAUGAUCUUGGUCUUGGCAAUGAUUUCUUGGAUAUGACACCAAAAUCACAGACAACGAAAACAAAAACAAAUAAGUUGAACUAUGUCAAACUGGAAAGCUCUUGCAAAGCAAAGGAAUAAUCAACAAAGUGAAAAGACAACAUAUGGAAUGGUAGAAAAUAUUUGCAAACCAUGUGUCUGACAAGGGGUUGCUAUCCAAAACAUAUAAGCAACUCCUACAACUCAACUCAACAGCAAAAAAACUAAUAACAUGACUUUAAAAUGGGCAAGGAUCUGAGUAGACAUCUUUCAAAAGAAAACAUACAAAUGGCCAAUAGGUAUAUGAAAAAAUGCUCAAUGCCACUAAUCAGGGAAAUGCAAAUCAAAACCACAAUGAGAUAUCGCUUCACACAUGUCAGGAUGCCUAUUAUCAAAUAAAAGACAACAAGUGGUUGGCAAAGAUGUGGAGAAAACUGGAAUCUUUGUAUACUGUUGGUGUUAAUGCAAAAUGGUGCAACUGCUAUGGAAACAUGGUGUAUAUAUUCAUCUAUAUUUGUAUAUAUGUAUAUGCAUAUUAUAUAUACAUGCAUAUAUAUAUGCACACAUAUAUGCACACACACAUGCACAAUGGAAUAUUGCCUUUUUUAAAUGCCAAGAUAAGAAACAA